ACUCUGCAGCUGGUCGCCAGGGACCCGGUCCCUCCUGCGCGCCCAAGUGAUGGAGGGGAAGAGAUUCGCUUAGACACACACACGCGCACACAGCUGGGCACGUCUCCGGGAGGCAGCUGCCGGCUCGGGCGCUCUGGGGGCCGGGCGGCGGCCGUGACAGCGCCAGCCGCGGGGAGCGGGGCGCCCGCACAGCUUGGCACCGGAGGCUCGAGGACGCAGGAAGGGAAGAUCCCAGUCACACUGAGUGUUGCUCUUUUGGGCGGAUUGGGAGGGAGCGGGCUGCCCGAGGAGCUGUCACCGAGGACGCCCGAAGUCUCGCCCUCUGCGCGCAGGGUCCGGGGCUGCGCCGGUGCCCUCGUGGGGCAAGGAGGAUGCGCACCUCCCCCCGCAGAGCGGCUGCGGUCUCCGGCACUGCGCGGACUCCGGCUCCUGCGGCCGCCCGUGCCGUGCCCGCGCCACGGGAGCGCGCCCUGCCGCACCUGGUUCCAGCCUCUCGGGGAAGUGCAGGAAACGCGCCCUAAACUCCACUACUUCUCGCCCGCCUGCCCCCCCGCCCGGCUCCCCGCCUCAGACCUCGCCGCCGCCGCCGCCGCCGCCGCCGCCUGCGUGUGGGGCCCGCUCGCGUCUUACUCACACGCGCCACGCACAGCCCUGUUGGUUUGCUCUCAUUCACGCCGACUCGCUCUCCGCCGAGCCUAGCCCGGGCAUCCGAAACUACUGGACCAACUGCCGUCCGGACCGCAGCAGCGGCCGGGUGACCCCCACGCGACCCGCCGCCGACCCCCGCGCCCUGAGGCUCCCGCCCGCGCCGCCACCGCCGGGGACCACGGUGAGCAAGGCGCGCUGCCCGCCUCGCGCGGGGGAGGGGCUUUGAGACCUCUAGAUUUGGGGGGAAAUGAGAAGGGGCAAAUCGCCAAAGGGAAGCAUCCGGGUGAUGCCAGCAAAAAAGCACUUUGUGGGGUUCGGUUCUCCUGGGCGCUGCCUGGGGAAGACUUUUGAGAGGUUUGCUUAGGACCAGAGGUUAAACUAGUGCGAGAUGAGAAACGGCGGGGGCAAUUCCUGGGGUAAAAUUAGACAGAAGGUGUCAGUCAGCCUGCCUGUCUGUUUCUCUCUCAGUCUCUCCCAGAGCGCUGGGUAGCGCUCUCUUUGAGGGAGAAAGGGAACACGCGUUUACUGCGCUCGCCAGAGUUUAGGGGUUCGCGUUCGGUCACUUCUGGGGUGGCUGUGGAGCUGUUUGGAGCGCGAGGGCAGCUUUGGGACAGUGGGGGCCUGCGAGGCCCCAGCAGAGGACAGGCAGAGGGCAGGCAAAGAACAGGCAAAGGCUAAGUUAACAUGUGGGUGGGGUUUUCUCUUCCCAGCUGGCCCCCCCCACACCCCUCACAGCCCCACUUUAUGCAUCUCUUCCCACCCAACACACACGCGCGCGCGCGCGCGGGAUGGAUGCAGUCGAAGGGUGGUCAUACUGUUACUACAAACAAGUCUGAGAGGUCGCUGUCGCUACUCACUGGAGCGCUGAGACUCCUGCUCCUGUUACUUGGGCGACCACCUUGGUUUAGGGCAACCUGCAAGGAGCGUCCAGCUUAAGGUGGAUGUCUUUACCUGGAGGUUCCAAGCGCCCAGCAAACAAACAACUCCGGAGUCACUUCACCUUGAGAUAAUCAGAUACUCACUGUCUUCAGCAUUGGUGUCUUCUAUUCUCAACGGCAUUUCUGGUGGCCACCCCAGGAGUCUCCCUGACCUGUUUUAAAACCCUUGGAAAUUAAGGAGAGAAUCCACUACAUAUAUUCCUUUGAAAGUUUCCACCAUAUAUGUUCAAAAAUUGCUGAAUGAGCACAAGGAUUUGAAGGUGCUAAAGCAAGGGAUAAACCAAAAGGACAGCCAGUAGGUGAGGAGAGGCCAUGGAAUACCCGCCAACAAGAUAAUCAUCGCUGGAAUAAUAGGGACCUGUCUGAAUGUAGGUGCGGUGGCUCAUGGCUGUAAUCCCAGCACUUUGGGAGGCCAAGGUGGGAGAAUCACUUGAGGUCAGGAGUUCAAGACCAGCCUGGCCAACAUGGCUGCAGCAGUCCUGAAGGUUGAUGGAGGGCCAUGCUAUUCAAACAGCAGGCGUGGCUGAGACAGAAGCUCCUGGUGCUGGGAAGCCUUGCCGUUGGGAGUCUCCUGUAUCUAGUCGCCAGAGUUGGGAGCUUGGAUAGGCUACAACCCAUUUGCCCCAUUGAAGGUCGACUGGGUGGAGCCCGCACUCAGGCUGAAUUCCCACUUCGCGCCCUGCAGUUUAAGCGUGGCCUGCUGCACGAGUUCCGGAAGGGCAACGCUUCCAAGGAGCAGGUUCGCCUCCAUGACCUGGUCCAGCAGCUCCCCAAGGCCAUUAUCAUUGGGGUGAGGAAAGGAGGCACAAGGGCCCUGCUUGAAAUGCUGAACCUACAUCCGGCAGUAGUCAAAGCCUCUCAAGAAAUCCACUUUUUUGAUAAUGAUGAGAAUUAUGGUAAGGGCAUUGAGUGGUAUAGGAAAAAGAUGCCUUUUUCCUACCCUCAGCAAAUCACAAUUGAAAAGAGCCCAGCAUAUUUUAUCACAGAGGAGGUUCCAGAAAGGAUUUACAAAAUGAACUCAUCCAUCAAGUUGUUGAUCAUUGUCAGGGAGCCAACCACAAGAGCUAUUUCUGAUUAUACUCAGGUGCUAGAGGGGAAGGAGAGGAAGAACAAAACUUAUUACAAGUUUGAGAAGCUGGCCAUAGACCCUAAUACAUGCGAAGUGAACACAAAAUACAAAGCAGUAAGAACCAGCAUCUACACCAAACAUCUGGAAAGGUGGUUGAAAUACUUUCCAAUUGAGCAAUUUCAUGUCGUCGAUGGAGAUCGCCUCAUCACGGAACCUCUGCCAGAACUUCAGCUCGUGGAGAAGUUCCUAAAUCUGCCUCCAAGGAUAAGUCAAUACAAUUUAUACUUCAAUGCUACCAGAGGGUUUUACUGCUUGCGGUUUAAUAUUAUCUUUAAUAAGUGCCUGGCGGGCAGCAAGGGGCGCAUUCAUCCAGAGGUGGACCCCUCUGUCAUUACUAAAUUGCGCAAAUUCUUUCAUCCUUUUAAUCAAAAAUUUUACCAGAUCACUGGGAGGACAUUGAACUGGCCCUAAAAUAAUAUGUCAUACAACACUAUGUGUUGUGCCUGGAGACACACAAUGUCUCCUGUAGAUUAAAAUAUGCACUUUUCCUAGGCAGAGCUAUCCAAGUCAUUUUUCCAUGUAUAUUUGUACAUACGCAGUGUGUGACCAAAUAUAAGAUCAGUUCUUUUUCUACUGAAAAUUUACGAAAAAAAAAAAAUUGCUGUCUGCAUAGUCGCAUCUUUUAAGCUAUUUACAAAAGAGAAGAGGUGGUGGUAUUGGGGGAAAGUGACUUCAGCUAUUCUCAAAGAGUUAGUCUUCCUUUGAUUCAGAAUUUGUCACCCGCCAUUUUCAUAGAUUUAAGCCAAAAGAUAAAUGUGUGAAAAUGUACCAAUGGCUGCGAAGCUUCAGGAAGUAGAGGAUCCAGUGAUGCAUUUUUUUUUUCCUAAGGGAAAGCUGGCUCUUUAAUUCAGAUGCUGAAUUGGUGCCAUGAAAACAGAAAAUGCUAUUUUCUUAUUAUUUAAAAGAACGUCUUAUCUCAUAAAAUUGACAUUGUUCCAAAGUUCUUGUGGUGAUUUUGCACUAUUGUUUUCUCGUAUGGACCAUGGUGUCACUUGUAGCAUGUCAAUCACACAUUGGAAAGUCAAGUCCUUUUACUUCCAUGUUGUAUGUCAACAGAGAGAAAUGUCAUGUACAUAAUGUAUAUUGUUGUAAAUACUGGUUUCACACUAAGUAAUUCUAUUUUGUAAACUGAAUAUGGCUAUUUAAUUUAUUGUGAAAAUUAAAUUUAUUGUGGUAUUUAAAAAUGGAAUGGAUUAAAAUUACUCUAUGUGCAAUUUUUUUUUUUUUUACUCAUUUUGUUUUACGUGCCCCCUGCUGGCUUCCAAAAUGGAAGCUGUUUACGUGCAUAUGAGAGCACUUGGAAAGAUGUGCUUCCCUGCUGGAUUUCUGUACCCCAGUGAAAAUGUAUUUAUGAAGUGAGGUUGAGUAUAUUAAAAAAGAAAAACCUCAACCAUCUGGAAAUCAAGUAUAAUAGCCACCUCAAAGAACCCUAGUGCUGCUCUGCUACAACUUUGUAACAAUUAAUUUACUCGCAGUUGCUGCUGCUCAGGAAGAGAGACAAGGAAUAUUUUAACAGAAUCAAGGCAUAGAAGAAUCACCAUUUUAUUUGAACCUCUAAUCAGAGUCAGACCAGUAGAGAAAUUAAAUAAGAUUAGAAAACUCUGUACUGAAAGCUGCUGAUGCUUCAAAAAUGAAAACAAGAUCUCACAACUCUCCCUGUUAGUUGAAAAUAUAUCAAUUUGCUCUGAAAGGAUUCAGCUGCCUAGUGUUGCCAUUACUAACAUAAACAUAUGGCUCAUAUUUCCAUCCAGAGAAAUUAAUGCUAAAUUGGUGCCUCGCUAACAUCAGAUACACUGUAUUAUGCUUAAAUAUAUUCAGUAAAAUGUGGAAAGGGGUAUUAACAACGACAACAAAAAGAUGGAUUUUUUUUUUCUCACAAUCACAGUUGCUAAUCCAGUGGGAGAUGUUUGAGAGAGUUUUGUUCAACAUCACAGUGAGAGUGCCUAGGGAAAUCAGAAAAUUACAAUGGAUUCCCCUUUGAUUGUAAUAAGUGUUGAUUUUCUCCAUGAGUUGUUUAUCCUGUCUAGUGAUUUGAUGGUGAACUUUUCUAAAUAAAUAGCCCUUUCCCCUCC